GUCACUUCCGGCGCGAGAGGCCGGGCAGGCCGGGCAGGGAGUGCGGGUCGGUUCUGCGUGCGCUGCCGGACGAGGCUCCCGCCGCCGAUUGACCCGCGCUCCGCCCGUAGUCGGGCCGGUGAGUGCCCGCGAGCCCAUCCGUGUGCCCUGGGAGCUGAGGAGAGGGACCCCUGAGAGGGAAGGAUAACCGGAAGUGGGGACCAGAGGAGCGAGAGACCCCAGGAAAUGGGGACACCUGGGGAGGGGGUGACAGCCGGAAGUGGGGGCCUCGGAAGGUUGUCCACGGGAUAUGGGGUCUCGGGGGCUCUAGGAGAGAUGGCUUCCUGACCUCUCCUUGUUGAGAGGAAGGGGUGGAAAGGAAAGUGAUGCUCCAGAAAGGAUGGGCUCCAGGUGGGGGAGAUCUUUGGCUUCACCGUUACCAAUGGUGUCUGCAUCUCACUCAUAUGUCCGCCUGUCAGCUCAUUCACCAGCCUGUGACUGAGUCCUGCUGAGCGCUCGGCACUGCUGAGUCCCUGGAGAGUCAACAUGAAGCUCCAGGUGGAGGGUACAGAUUAGAAGCCCAGGGUGGGGCUAGACGCAUCCUUGCUCUGCCUCACCGGGUGUGCCCCCUUGGGCGAAUCGCUUAACCUAUAUCCUCCGCUGAUGUGUACAGACCACUGCCAUGUGCCCGGCACUGGGGGUGGCAGUGGACAUGGCAGACAAGCCCUCUGCCCUCGUGGAACUUAGAUUCUAGGGGACAGUCCUUUUUGUCCUCCUUUGUAAAAUGGCAACAGUAAUAGCGCUCUCACCAAAUAACGUGAAGAUUAAAUGAGGAAAUGGGUAAAGGGCUUAGCAAUGCUUGAUACAUGGUAAAAUGCUCAAGUAUGCAUUCUCUUCAUUCCACUAUAAUGUAAGCUUUAUUAGGCAAGGAAUUGUAUUGUUUGCGUCUGUGUUCCCAGUGCCUGUGAGCACAGUGCCUGACAUAUAUGGUAGGUGAUCGGUAAUUAUUUGAUAAAUGAGUGCGUGGUGAAACUGACUCUAGAUAAAUGCCCAUAGCAUUGGACUGUAAUUUCUAAAAAAGAAAUAGGAACCCAGUUCUGUGGAAAACUGGAGGGAAUCACCCUCAGGGAGUUUGGGAAGGAUUCACUGAGGUGGUGACAUGGCAGCUGAGCCUGAGCUGUCAAGUUAGGAACAAAUUAGAAGAGGAAAUUCCAGGCAGAGUGUAUCAGAAGUGCACGAGUUAUUCCAAGGAUGAUGGGUUAUUAGUUUGUUUUGACUGGCAUUUAAUGUGCAUCAAGGUGGGGUGCGAUGGAAAAUGAGGCUGGAGAGGGGCUUUGAGGUGAGGCUUGUACCUUGUGAACACUGAUGUUUGAUGGGAUUGCAGGCAUCUCUUGGUUACUUCCAUAGAAACAAAGCCAUAGUUGUUCCAUUCCUCACUUAGCAUACCUGUGCCAACCAGACUAAAGUCAUUCAACAAAUAUUUAUGGAGUGCAGAUUAUGUGUCUAACACCAUGUUAGGCGCUGGGUUUCAGGUGAUGAACAAGACAAACUUGGAUGUUGCUCACAAAUUGCCAACAGACAAUUGCAACAGGGUGGGAGAAGUGCGGGGGAGGCACCUAACCUGGCUGGGGGUCAGUGAAGGCUACCUACUCCAGGCCACCAGCAUCUCUCAGCUGGAUUAUUGCAAUAGCCUCUAAAUGGUCUGCUUCAGUCCUCACUCCCUUAGAGUCCAUUCUCAAGACAGCAGAUUGGUCCUUUUAAAAUAUAUUUUUAUUUAUUUAUCUAUCUAUCUAUUUAUUUAUUUAUUUAUUUAUUUAUCUGAGAUAGCGUCUCGCCCUGUCGCCCAAGCUGGAGUGCAGUGACAUGAUCUCGGCUCACUGCAACCUCCGCUUCCUGGUUUCAAGCGAUUAUCCUGCUUCAACCUCCCAAGUAGCUGGCACUACAGGCCCGCACCACCAUGCCUGGCUAAUUUUUGUAUUUUUAGUAGAGACAGGGUUUCACCAUGUUGGCCAGGCUGGUCUCGAACUCCUGACCUCAGGUGAUCCAUCCACUUCAGCCUACCAAAGUGUUGGGAUUACAGGCAUAAGCCACCACACACAGCCCAAGAAAAAAUUUAAAAAUUAGCCAGGCGUGGUGUGUGCCUAUAGUCCCAGCUACCUGGGAGGCUGAGGCAGGAGGAUUGCUUGAACUUAGGAGUUCGAGGUUGCAGAGAGCUAUGAUUGCGCCACUGCACUUCAGCCUGGGUGACAGAGCAAGACCCUGUCUCUCUCUUAAACAAAAAAGUGCAUGAGUUCAGGUCCUCUAAGAAGCAGACACUAGGAUGAGGUUAGACGUGCUAGAAAUGUAGAGGCAACCCUUGCGAAGGACAGCACCUGGGAAGGGAGCUGGAGAAGUCAGGAAGAGCCACUGGCAGUGAUGCAGAUCAGCUCCUGUGAAGGAGGUUUGGGCAGCAAGUCUCUGACUGCAGGGCAGUCCCAACAAAGGUUUGGCCAGGCCCUCAAGCAAACGCUGCCUGUUAGAGGAGUCCUAUGUCUCACUAAAUCAUUGGCUAGGAGCAGUGAGGCCACAGAAGGGCUGUGGAAAGUUCUGGCUUCCCCUGGAUAGUGGAUCUAGAGGGACAGCCACUGGGGCCCUUUAUCAAUUACGUUUUCCCAGCAGAUCUGACCGGCACAUAUUCCCGACUGCCACGAUAAGUUACAUGGGUGUGUAGUAAAAAAUUCAAACAGUAUAGUAAAAAUCCUCUUUCUCAUCUUAAAUCUUCACUUGUCCAGUUCUGUUCCAAGAGAUAACCAUUGGGACCUUGGUAGCUAAUGUCCGAAGAAAGUGACUCUCUGAGAACCAGCCCUUCUGUGGCCUCACUCUCUGAAAAUGAGCUGCCACCACCACCUGAGCCUCCGGGCUAUGUGUGCUCACUGACAGAAGACCUGGUCACCAAAGCCCGGGAAGAGCUGCAGGAAAAGCCGGAAUGGAGACUUCGAGAUGUGCAGGCCCUUCGUGACAUGGUGCGGAAGGAGUACCCCAACCUGAGCACAUCCCUCGACGAUGCCUUCCUGCUGCGCUUCCUCCGAGCCCGCAAGUUUGAUUACGACCGGGCCCUGCAGCUCCUCGUCAACUACCACAGCUGUAGAAGAAGCUGGCCCGAAGUCUUCAAUAACUUGAAGCCAUCAGCCUUAAAAGAUGUCCUUGCUUCCGGGUUCCUCACCGUGCUGCCCCACACUGACCCCAGGGGCUGCCAUGUCGUCUGCAUCCGCCCAGACAGAUGGAUACCAAGCAACUAUCCAAUUACUGAAAACAUCCGAGCCAUAUACUUGACCUUAGAAAAACUCAUUCAGUCUGAAGAAACCCAGGUGAAUGGAAUUGUAAUUCUUGCAGACUACAAAGGAGUGAGUUUAUCAAAAGCAUCUCACUUUGGCCCUUUUAUAGCCAAAAAGGUGAUUGGCAUCCUCCAGGAUGGUUUCCCCAUUCGGAUAAAAGCAGUCCAUGUGGUGAAUGAACCUCGAAUAUUUAAAGGCAUUUUUGCCAUCAUAAAACCAUUUCUAAAGGAGAAAAUAGCAAACAGAUUCUUCCUCCAUGGGUCUGACUUGAACUCUCUCCACACAAACCUUCCAAGAAGCAUCCUCCCCAAGGAGUAUGGGGGCACGGCUGGGGAGCUGGACACUGCCACCUGGAACGCGGUACUGCUGGCUUCAGAAGACGAUUUUGUGAAAGAGUUCUGCCAACCUGUUCCUGCCUGUGACAGCAUCCUGGGCCAGACGCUGCUGCCCGAGGGCCUGACCUCAGAUGCACAGUGUGACGACUCCUUGCGAGCUGUGAAGUCACAGCUGUACUCCUGCUACUAGCCCGUCCCCCAGGGUCACCAUCUUUAAUUCUUUUCCUUCUUUUCUUUGGAGAGGCACAAGGAGAAUUUAAGGGUCCAUGGAUUCAGUCUUGCUCCUUGUAAUUAAACUGCAGGAUGGAGGAACAGCCUGAGAUAUGAGCAUGAGCCCAUUUUGGGGUAAGCCUUUGGUUACUUUAAUUACUCCAUGGAAGACAUGGAAAAUGUCCCCACUGAUUCUUAAACAUUUGGAAUCCCAGUCUGCAACUAUUAAUCUGGAGGCUAUAUCUAUUUUGUUUUGCUUUUUGGUUGGGGGGUGGUGAUCUGGUUCUUACACAUCUUGGAAGCAAGAACAAUCAGGACCAAAGUCACUUUGAUCCCACUUUUCCAGGAGAAAAACCACCUGUUUGGCCAGUGAGAACUACUUGUAUGAAAUAAUUUGGCCAAACCUUCAGUGUGACCAAAUGUGAGACUGGGAGUUUGUGUUUUUCACAGGAACCCUAAGUAUAGACCUCUGCUGCUCAUCAGGAAACUUACUGGAGAUGAAGGCCCCAGCUGUUGUCACCGGGUUUGGAAAGCACCUUAACUGAAUCAUGUAAGCAUCAGGACAUAAGCAGCACUUUGUGGUCAAAUGUGGAAGCCGGAGACUUCAAAGCACCUCUGGGACCCACUGGUUGAAGUUUGCAAUAGAAACUUAAGUUUUCCCAAAUCCAUAAAGCCUUAGCCCUGGUUCUCAAUAGAAUCAGGGACCUAGCAGGAAAUGAUUUUACUCAACCUAAAAUGCUGGAUCCCAGGCCCGUGUAGCUAUAAGAAUUCUGGCCUGGAUCCCAGGUGUACAACUAUGGACAAGAUAUGGGCCUCUACUUUCUCCUCUAUAAAAUGAGGCUGGAUGAAAUGUCAGCUAGGGCCAUUUUGGCUGCUGAGGCUCUGGGAUUUGGUUUAGUUACUGAAUGUUAGAUUUUCUGCCUAGAAAGAUAACUAUCUAGAUACAAGUGGUUGGAUCCUGUUUUUGUUUGUGGUACAUGUGUCUUUCCAAGAGAGAUGUGUCACCAAUUAGCCCUGCCUUUAAAGAAACUAUUAUGUGUAUUCCUGGGACUCACUGACACCAAUUUUCUUUUUAUAGUGAUGGUUCAAUUUUGAAAAGAUGGCUUUUGUGAGGCCAGGUUAAGGUGACCAGGAUCUUGUAUGAUGAAUUCCUUCCAUCCCUGAGACUCUGGUACUAUAUUGUAAACCUGGCUACAGUAGUUAAUUACUUGAGAUUCUUUAAUUUUGGUCUCUGAGCUGGGCGUGGUGGUUCAUGCCUGUAAUCCCAGCACUUUGGGAGGCCAAGGUGUGCGGAUCACAAGGUCAGGAGUUCGAGACCCGCCUGGCCAAGAUGGUGAAACCCCAUCUCUACUAAAAAUACAAAAAUUAGCUGGGCGUGGUGGCGGGCUCCUGUAGUCCCAGCUACUCGGGAGGCUGAGGCAGAAGAAUCACGUGAACCCAGGAGGCAGAAGUGGCAGUGAGCCAAGAUCGCACCACUGCACUCCAGCCUGGGCGACAGAGCAAGACUCUGCCUCAAAAAAAAAAAAAAAAAAAAAAAAUUUUUUUUUUUUUGGUCUCUGGAAAUGAACACAAGGGCAGGUUAUUCCUGGGUCACUUCUGGGCCCCCCUGCCCUCCCAGCCCCACUUGAGUUUCUCUCUCUGGUGUGGGUGAACCAGUCAGCCUGAAUGUUCUGCAUUUCAGCACUUUAGAACCUCCCUGUGAAGAUUUUAGCCUUAGCCCAAACAUCAAAUUAGACGGUUCACAUGAUGGUUUUUGACCUAUUUCCUUUCUAAUGUAUUCCACAUGAUCAUGGUGUUAAAUAGUGAAAAGUACUGUGUUGUGUGUGCACCUUCUCCGUGCAUUUAUUAGACUAACCAGUCAAGCAGACAGCUCAGUUAGGGAGAAAACAAUACUCUGAAAUUUGAAGGCCAAUCUGUUGUUACUAAGCUGUUUAUCUCUAUUGCCUUUUUAAAUGUCUGGAUAAGUUGUUGGUGGAAAUUAAGUUACUUAACCUCAUUAAUACCAAUUCUAGAGAAAGUUCUUUUCACCAUGGAUAGUAACCCUGGAUCCUCUACGGUACUGGCUGAGCUGGAAGUGCCAAAAAGCACUCCUGGCUGCUUCUGGUUCCAUCUGAUGAUGAUGUGACACACACUGCUGAAAAGGCCCAAGCAGGGCAAGUGGGAUGGCUGAAGGAGGGAAGGAGGGGGUUCAGAACCCACUGGCCUGGAUGGGAGAACUGGGUGGAGGCUUCCCCAAGAGGGAAGACAGAUAAACAAAACAAAACAAAAACUGGGUAAAGAGGAAUGAAUCACUCAGCCCUGAUGUUUCAAUUCUACACUGCAUUCCUGGCCAGUCGCAUUUGUUUUAAUGCAGGCAUGGCCACAGCUCUCCUAGAGAAUUAUCUCAAAGACCAGAAGGGACCUGGAGAGGCCUAUUUCUUAGGUUUUUCCAGUUGGACAAGGAAGGAGUGGUUUCACUCAGCUUCUAGAAGGAGUUGGAGCCUAAGUUUAUCUGCCUCCGGGAGCUGCUUGCUUUGUUUUGGCUCCGAAGAGGUAUCAGAUAGUUUUGACACCUCAGGAAACUUGAACCAAGCUGUGAAACCAAGACCUCCCUGCGUGAAAAUCAAGGUGGUCUCCUUGUGGCUUCACCAGGAUGUUUGUGUCAGGCUGUCUCAGCAGGGUGGGGAAUGACCAGCCAGGGAGCACAGUGAGCCUUACUCAGCACUGGGGAGCGCACUGGUGAGGCAAACCCAUGAACCUCAAGAACUGGGAGUAUGUUCCUUCAGGGAGAAGUUCUGGCCCAUUGCACAAACACUUGGAAAUUAACUUUUCCCUAAAUUCAAGAUAGUGUGGUGUCGGAAGGAAAUGGGACAGUAAAUUAGGAGACGCGGGCUCCACCUUUACCUUACUACGUGGCCUUUGAUGAGCUGGCUUAACAUCCCUGAGUGAUUCCAUGAUAGAGAUCUAUACUCCAAACUUUAUUCCUGGUAUCUAGUUGGCUUCACUGCCACAGACACUGUACUCUCUCUUUUUAGAAGUUUUUUUCCUUUUUUUUCCCCCUCAAUUGGCUUAUUUAGUAAAUUUAGGUCUGAAUGAAUUGGUACCUAAAAGCUUCCAAAUCUAUACAUUUCAGAAUAUGGGAAUUUUCUUCCUCUUCUUCCCCCAUAUCCCAACAUGGAAUUCUGGAAAACUGUGCCUCUUCCCCUGUUCUGCCUUCAUGGGGGAGAGACUGGAUGAAAUCUACAAAAACAGCCAAAAGUGCCACCCUGGCUUCAUGUCUUGAAUUUCUAACUUGCUCUUGGCAAAGGUCGCUUUAUUUUUUAAUUUUUUUCCUUGCAUUUUCUUUUUUAUUCUAUUGCUGCUGCAAAAAUUAAGGCAAAAGUAGCUUUCGAUCUUUCAUAUUUCAUCCUGGUUUCACAAGGAGUCACUUAUCUUAGGAGGUCUGUAAGUCAGGUUACAAGGCCGGGAGCGGUGGCUCACACCUGUAAUCCCAACACUUUGAGCGGCUGAGGUGGGUGUAUCACCUGAAGUCCGGAGUUUGAGACCAGCCUGGCCAACAUGGUGAAACCCCGUCUCUACUAAAAAUACAAAAAAUUGGCUGGGCAUGGUGGUGGGUGCCUGUAAUCCCAGCUACUUGGGAAGCUGAAGCAGGAGAAUCACUUAAACCCAGGUGGCGGAGGUUGCAGUGAGCCGACAUCGCGCCAUUGCACUCCAGCCUGGGUGACGAGUGAAACUCCAUCUCAAAAAUAAAAAUUGAAAAAUCAGGUUACAAAACACCAUUUUUCCCGAAAUAAGACAAUAAGAGGCUUUUCUCUGAAUUCCUUUAUAUUGAGCCUUUCAGAAUUCUCCCUGGGUGGGCAAUUUCUUUAAAUAGUAUUUGACCCUCAGAUCAAUCCUGGGAAUUUUUUUCAUUUGGGUAGCAAAAGCUAGAGUAUUGCUGUGGCGAUUAUAAUACUUUUAAAAAGUUUUACCAUUUUAAAGUUGCCAACAUUUAAUUAAGGUUUUCCUUUGAAGCCUCCUUUAAUUUAGGGAGUAAAAUGUUAGCUAAACCAAUUAUAUACUAUAUACUAUACACUGUAUCUCCUGUGGCCAUGAGAGGUGUGGCUAUACCGAACAGAAACAUGCCUACUGUUCAGGAAAGAUGUCAGUUCUGGUAACACCUCUCUGUAUUGGGAUCUGUUAAUUUUGUAAAUCUAAAUUCUUCUGCUCUUGGCCAGGUGCAGUAGUUCAUGCCCUGUAAUCCUAGAACUUUGGGAGGCUGAAGGGGGGGCGGAUCAUUUGAGGUCAGGAGUUUGAGACCAGCCUGGCCAACAUGGUGAAACCCCAUCUCUACUAAAAAGUACAAAAAUUAGCUGGGUGUGGUGGUGCGUGCCUGUAAUCCCAACUACUUGGGAGGCUGAGGCAGGAGAAUCGCUUGAACCUGGGAGGCAGCGGUUGCAGUAAGCCAAGACUAUGCCACUGCACUCCCGCCUGGGUGACAAAGCAAUAUUCUGUGUCAAAUAAAUAAAUUCAUUCUUCUGCUCUCCUGACUUAGAGAAAUGGUUUGCUUAAAAUGCUAGUAACAAACAUCACAGUCAACAGGAGCUUGCUUCAUGCGAAGGAUCAAUGUGAUUUGUGGAUGGAGAUGAUAGUGAUGAAAUUCCUGUUUCAUGGGGCUGUUUUUCUUUUCAUCUCACUGGGCAGCAGGUUUAGUGAGGCAGUGAGAUGCUGCUGCUGUGGAUUCUUGUAGCUAUGCCUCGGCUUCUUGGCAUAUCAGGUAGGAACCUGUUACAAGUGAAAUACUUGAAACCUCUCUGACCAAGAGCCUCUGAUGGAGUGGGAGGUGAGCUAAUUCUCUGACCAGCUUGGGGCACUGUUUCAGCCACUGGUCACAUUCCUUGCUUCAAACUGAAAUUCAGUUUGGCUUUGAGUAUAGGGAUACAUGGUGGAUUCAUGUACUUCAGUGUUUGUUUUGACCAAAGUUUAUUUUUCUAGUGCAUUUUCUAAGUCAAAGUGGUGAAAAUAUGUAAUAAUUUUAGUAUGCAUGACUCAGUCUGAAACAAUAAAAAUCUCUGAAAAAUGUG